GCCUCUGGCUCUGAGGCGGCGGCGCCGGGCGCUGCGAAGGCUCGGCCGCUGUAGUCAGUGGUGUGGGGUGCGCAAGGGCACGGACCUCGGAGCUCUCCCCGCUUGCGCCGAGUUUCUCAGCGCCUUCCCCACCCAAACCGGGGUCUCGCAGUCGGAAGCACUCAGAGUGCAGCCCCGCGCGGGGCCGGUCGUAACCGCGCCGCGGGCCGGACGAUGCCCAAGAAGCUGCUGCUGUUGCCCCCGCCCUCCGCGUCCUCGGCUUUCCGCGUCCCGCGCGCCCGCCCCGUUCCCCCGCCGGCCAUGAACGCCGCUCGCACCGGCUACCGAGUCUUCUCGGCCAACUCCACGGCCGCCUGCACGGAGCUGGCCAAGCGCAUCACAGAGCGCCUUGGUGCUGAAUUGGGGAAGUCUGUUGUAUAUCAAGAGACCAAUGGAGAAACAAGAGUUGAAAUAAAAGAAUCUGUUCGUGGCCAAGAUAUUUUCAUUAUACAGACAAUACCCAGAGAUGUGAAUACAGCUGUGAUGGAGUUGCUCAUCAUGGCUUACGCACUGAAGACUGCCUGUGCCAGGAACAUUAUUGGGGUCAUCCCCUACUUCCCCUACAGCAAGCAGAGCAAGAUGAGGAAGAGGGGUUCCAUUGUGUGCAAGCUGCUAGCAUCCAUGCUGGCGAAAGCAGGUUUAACUCACAUUAUCACUAUGGAUCUUCAUCAAAAGGAAAUACAAGGCUUUUUCAGCUUUCCUGUGGACAACCUUAGAGCCUCACCUUUCCUGCUUCAGUAUAUCCAGGAAGAAAUUCCAAAUUACAGAAAUGCAGUCAUUGUAGCUAAGUCUCCUGAUGCUGCAAAGAGGGCCCAGUCCUAUGCGGAGAGACUGCGUCUGGGUUUGGCCGUCAUUCACGGGGAAGCUCAGUGCACGGAACUGGACAUGGACGAUGGUCGUCACUCCCCGCCUAUGGUCAAAAAUGCUACUGUGCACCCAGGCCUGGAGUUGCCAUUGAUGAUGGCCAAAGAGAAGCCACCGAUAACUGUAGUUGGAGAUGUUGGAGGCCGCAUCGCAAUCAUCGUGGAUGACAUUAUUGACGAUGUGGAGAGUUUUGUUGCUGCCGCGGAGAUCCUGAAAGAGAGAGGCGCCUAUAAGAUCUAUGUUAUGGCCACCCACGGCAUCCUGUCUGCAGAGGCCCCUCGCCUGAUUGAGGAGUCCUCCGUAGACGAGGUGGUGGUGACGAAUACUGUCCCUCAUGAGGUUCAGAAGCUGCAAUGUCCCAAGAUAAAGACUGUGGAUAUCAGUUUGAUUCUUUCUGAAGCCAUUCGGAGAAUCCACAAUGGAGAGUCCAUGGCCUACCUUUUCCGAAACAUCACUGUGGAUGACUAGCUUUCACGAGGGUCUCGACCCUGGACCUCCUGAGGGAAACAUGGAAAAAGCAGUGCCAUGAGUGAUACAGUGUUUCCUUGCAAGGGAGGACUCGAAACAGCCUGGAGUUAGAUAUCUUCUUUUGCCCGGAUUGAUGGGGAGGAGGGAUUAAAAGAGUCAGGAAGAAGACAGAGCUAAUGGAUAAAUAUCAUAACAUGGCCUUACAUGUCUGCUGUCAUCAGCCCUGUUCCUUAAAAGUUCUAGCUGCUUUCUUAAAAAUAAUCUGAAAAUCUUAUUGAUACUAAAGAGGAGUUAAAGGCACAUAAAGUCUUAACUCUAUAAUGUUCAUUUAGUUGUUUCAGCUCCAGGGAAAUGGAGGUAUUGAUGUUGAACCUGGUUAGGGAAGCUGAGCGCCUGUGGCCCUAUUACUAUCCAGUUGGCCUCUCCCAAAUCAACUUCAAGUCUUUUAUAGAGAAUCGUAUUUUUCUUUCAGAAAUUGUUAUGCCUACAGCCAUUGAAAAAUGAAGCAUUCAUGUUGUUACAUCUUCCAAGGAUGUCAGAUUAGAAAAUAGCAUCCCACCUCUGGGUAUCUGAGUGGCUCUGAAGUUGCAAAUAAAAUAAUUUGUUGUCUUGCUAGUCUUUUCAUUAGACAGCAGAAGACCAUGGAUACAGAACAGCAGUCAGGUCUGUGGCUGGACACAAACACUUUCCCAGGUUCCACCCUCUUCCUAAGUGUUGAAGCUAAAUCCUUGUUGAAUACUGUAUUUUAAAUCUUUAAAAAAAAAAAAAAAAAGUCUAGGUGUGGUGGCUCACACCUAUAAUCUGAGUACUUUGGGAGGCUGAGGCAAGGAGGAUUGCUUGAGCCCAGGAGUUUCAGACCAGCCUGGGAAACAUGGCGAAACCCCCAUGUCUACAAAAAAUACAAAAAUUAGCCAGGCAUUGGUAGCAUGUGCCUGUAGUUCCAGCUACCUUGGGAGGCUGAGGUGGGAGGAUUGCCUGAGCCAAGGAGGUUGAAGCUGCAGUGAACUAUGAUUGUACCACUGCCAUCCAUCCUGGGUGACAGAGCAACACCCUGUCUCAAAAAAAAAAAACAGGCCAGGGAUCGUGUCUUAUGCCUGUAAUCCCUGCACUUUGGGAGGCCGAGGCAGGUAGAUCACCUGAGGUCAGGAGUUUGAGACCAGCCUGGCCAACAUGGCAAAACCCCGUCUCUACUAAAAAUACAAAAAUUAGCCUAGCUAAGUUAAAAGCAUAAAAAGACUACAAAGAGGCCAGGCAUCAUGGCUCACGCCUGUAAUCCCAGCACUUUGGGAGGCCGAGGUGGGCAGAUCACUUGAGGUCAGGAGUUUGAGACCAGCCUGGCCAAUAUGGUGAAACCCUGUCCCUACUAAAAAUACAAAAAUUAGCCGGGUGUUGGGGGAGGGGGUGCACGCCUGUAAUCCCAGCUACUCGGGAGGCUGAGGCAGGAGAAUUAAUUGGUUGAACCCAAGAGGCAGAGAUUGCAGUGAGCUGAGAUUGUGCCACUGCACUCCAGCCCAAGUGACAGAGCAAGAUUCCAUCUCAAAAAAAAAAAAAGACUGCAAAGAACUAGUUAUUUUGAUAACCCCUUAAAGGCCUACUGUGUCCCAAGUUAUUGGAAUAUAAUGAUGAUCGAAAAUCCUUCAAUUAAAUAAACAGUACCUCUCAGGCUGAAGUGAAAAAUCUGAACUUGAACAGUAGUUAAAAUAGUACAGUUAUUCCUUACAAUCCAUGGGUGAUUGGUUCCAGGACUCAACCUCCUGCCCAUGGAUGUGCAAGUCCCUGAUAGAAAAUGGUGUAGUAUCUGCAUAUAAGCUAUGCACAUCCUGGAUGACUUGUAAUACCUACUGCAAUAUCCUGUGUAGAUGGUGGUCAUGCUGUAUUAUUUAGAGAAUCAUGACAGGAAUCUGUACGUGUUCAGUCGUGGUUGGUUAAAUCUGCAGAUGCAGAGCUCACGGAGGAGGCUGGCCAUGCAUGGCACACAUUCAUAGGUUCUCUUUAAGUAGCCUUGCUGUGCUUCUGUUAGGAAGUUUUAUUUAUACGUUUUUGGGAAGAAUCUUGUAUGGGGAA